UAACCCCUUGUAGUUACAAAGCAGUAAACCAAAUCUUUUACAGUCUGUUUUGCCUUCAGGUAACUUCCUGUUAAAGAUGAAGAAGGUAUCUUCCCCUAAGCGUCCUGGUAGAUUAUUUUACUGUGCAAAUCAAGACUGUUACCUAUUUUAGGAUGUAUGAACGUGUGGUCACAAAAGUGAUGAGGUUUUGUACAGACACUUAAGUUAAUUCUUGUAAACAAAAUAUAGAAAGCAGCUUCUACUUUUUCAAUUCGUAUGUUGUAUUUAAGAGAAAUUAACCAGAGAAUAAUUUAUUCAUCUUAGUAAGCCAUACUACCAUCUCUCUUUAUGUUCAUUCUAGUUCCUAAGUUGUUCUUCCAACUAGGUCUAGAAAAUAGUUGUUUUUAAUUAUAGAAGAUUGUUAAUAGUGUUAUGGCCUUUUUAAGGAGCUAAAGGAGAAAUUUUAUAAAAUUGGAAAUUGGUAGCUACUCCUUUUUAUUUUACUUAUUUAUUUUUUUAGACAGAGUCUCGCUCUGUUGCCCAGGCUGGAGUGCAGUGGCGCAAUCUUGGCUCACUGCAAGCUCCAUCUACCAGGUUCACGCCAUUCUCACGCCUCAGUCUCCCAAGUAGCUGGGAUUACAGGCGCCCAUCACCACGCCCGGCUAAUUUUUUUUUAAAUUUUUGAUAGAGACGGGGUUUCACCAUGUUAGCCAAGAUGGUCUCAAUCUCUUGACCUCGUGAUACGCCCGCUUCAGCCUCCGAAAGUGCUGGGAUUACAGGCAUGAGCCACUGUGCCCGGCCUACUCUUGUCUUUUUAAAAUGUUACCUGGAAGUAGAAGCUCCAUUAGAAUUCCAGGAGGUUAAAAUCUAAUAGGCUGAACCAAUAAUUUAAUGAUGGUAGAAUUGAUGUAAAUAGAUUUCACUAUUGUGGAAGAAUGUGAAUGCUCGUUUAUGGCAGGGUUGCCACAGUGUCUGCCAGGGUAUUAUUAGGUGUUACUUUAAAGGAUUCAGUGGGGUUGUCAGUUGUUGUACCCUUUAUGGUCUCAUUUUGAACAGUUAAAAAUAAAGAUUUAAUUUGUGUUAGUAAUUCUUCCUUGUGUCACUGUAAACCUACACAUUCUACUAAGAGAAAGUCUGUCUUUCAGCUGUAGAUGUUCUUUCUUAAAUGUAUGUCAAGGUGGGUGAUAGUUUUAGACCCUUCUAAAAAUUCAAGACUGUGACAUAUUGAUCUCAAUUUAAUAUCACAUGUGCUUCUAUAAAAUCCAUUCUAGUCAUUUGCCUAAUAUGUUUAUGAUGCCACAAAUCAAAACACUCUUGUUUUAUUUUAAUUUUUUAACCUUGAAGGAAUUUUUUUAGAAGAACUGCCUCAGCAUAGUUGAUGUUUUAAUUCUACAGUAAAAGUCUCAUUAACUAUUCUUUAGCAUGAAUGAGUCUUCUGAAUAGUAGGUCAAUUUUAGAAGUUUAAACAUUUUAAAAGCUUCUGUAGGAUUUGUGCUGGUUGAAUAAGUUGAUUGUAAAAAUGUUCACUGAAAGUUUGUUCAACUGAAAGGAAAUAGACAUCUUUAAAUUGGUGUAUUUGUGUGAGUGCUAAAAAUUUGUGCAUAUCAGCUUGUUUUCCCUGGGGUAUGAAUAAGGUAUAUGUGUGGAUGUUGAGCUUGAUUAGGAGGAAUGAUUACAUGGGCAAGACAAUCUUUCCCCAUAGUAUCCUGCAACCAAAAAAAAAAAAAAAGGAAAAUCCUUUCCUCCUCUCACCAAGUCAUAGUUUCAAUAAAGACCAAAGAACCAAUGCAUACUUAGAUUAAAGUUUGCUUACUUUUAUGAAACUUUGAAAACUUUUCAUAGGGUUCCUUUACUAAUGGUAAAACUGUUCUCAGGAAACAGUCAUUGUAUACAUUAGGGAUUAGGUUUGGAUGUAACAGAGACCUGCCUGUGGUGGUUUAAACACAUGAGGCUUUCUGUUCUCAUGUGAAAGAACUCUGCAAGUUGGAUAUCUGUGGCUGUUAUGGAGGCUCCUUAAAGUAAGUCAUCACACACUUUUCAUUUUCUGCCAUCUGUCAUGUGGCUCCAUGGUUAACUCAUAGUCUAAGAUGGCUGCUGUUUGAACUUGGGUCAGUAGGAAGGAGGAAAGCGAGAACAAAGAAGAACAAAUAAGGUACCUCUUUUCUGGAGCCUUCCCAGAGGUCCCACACAGUAUUUCUUCAUACAUUUAAUUGGCUAGAACUUAAUUGCAUGGCCACAUGCGAUAACACUGGGAAAUAUAGUCUUGACCAGAGUAUGCUGGAACUCUAGUGAAACUGGCAUUCUGUUACCUACGGGGAAAGGGAAGAAUGGAGUUUGAGUCAGCAAUGAGGCUCCGCCAUGUUCAUUUAGCCAACAUUUACGAAUAAUUAUUAUAGUUAGUAUAUUUAACCAGAUAUUGGAGACACAAUAUUAAGAAAAACAGUCUCCUUUAAUAUGAGGAUCUCUAGGCCUCUGGGAGAGAUGGAAACAUGAAUAGUUAUUUAUAAUGCAACUGGUUAUUUCUACAUAGACUUCUAUAGAUACAAUAUCCAAAAAAGAAGAUAAUGGCCUAUAAGGUGUACAAAAAGCUAACUGAGCUCUAGAGGGGAAUUGAUUAAUAUGCAGUGGCUCAUUUAUAAUUUAACACUAAAUGAUAAAUAGAUUGUGAUAGUUAUAAGCACAUUUGAUUUCCAAAAGGGGUUUUUAAUCCUAUACCUGACUUUCUGUGGCAUCAAAUAUAAAUAGAUGUAUACUAUUUUUGUAAAUAAAUUAUAUACUCUCAUAAUCAGAUGGUGCCAUGUAGCCCACAGAGCCAAAUUAUGAAAACAAGACGUAUUCAGUGAAUUCAUCUAAUUACUGAAGCAGAUAAGGGCCAUGCAAUGUUAGAGUGGAUAGGUUUGUUGGAAAUAACCCAGCAUGCCUCCUCAUUUGAUGGGUACAUGAAUUGAGGCCCCCAGACACUGCCAGACUGACAAGACAAGUUAGUGGGAAACAGACUAGGACUCUCAUCGGUUUCUAACACCUGUUUUAAGCUGCUGUUUCGCAGCAAAAUAAAGCCAUUAAAAGGUGUUCUUUGGUGCUGUCCUCCUUUUCCUUUAAGUGAUAAGGUCCAGUGAGAAUUAGUAGGGGAUCCAUCUGGCAGUUUUCAUUCUUUGUUUGCCUUUUCUUUGGUUGUGUUUCUGGAAGGGAGGAAGAAAGCAGGGGGCCCAGAGCUCAUUUUAUUUUUAUCCAUUCAUUAGAUGAAAUAAUGUCUACCUUUUAUAGCAGUUGUGGUGGUUCCCAAAUGCAUCUGUCAUACAUAACCUUUUAAAAUGCUUCCUGACUUUGAAAGCAGUGGUUAUACAUGAUGGACAUUGCUCACCUAACAACUUUUGUAGGAAUAAUGAUUUUGUGGGUUUUUUUGUUUUUGUUUUUUUUUGAGACAGAGUCUCGCUCUGUCGCCCAGGCUGAAGUGCAGUGGUAUGAUCUCAGCUCACUGCAAGCUCCGCCUCCUGGGUUCAGGCCAUUCUCCUGCCUCCACCUCCCAAGUAGGUGGGACUACAGGCGCCCGCCACCAUGCCUGGCUAAUUUUUUGUAUUUUUAGUAGAGACGGGGUUUCACCGUGUUAGCCAGGAUGGUCUUGAUCUCCUGACCUUGUGGUCCACCCUUUUGGCCUCCCAAAGUGCUGGGAUUACAGGCAUGAGCCACUACGCCCAGCCAAUUUUGUGGGUUUAUUACAGUAAAAUCUCCAAAAGCUUAAAUCAUUAUUGGCUGUAUUAUCAUUUGUGAGGUGUUUAUUUAUAGUAUGUUCCUACUAUGUUGUAGGUACUAUUAUUAGGUGCUAGAAAUCAAAGAUAAUUUGAUUUCAAUUAAAAGAGAUAUUCAGAAUAAUGGCCGGGGUGGCGGAUAGACUAUAUACACAUAAUACAUUGGGAAGACACAAAUACCACCGGACAGAGUACUGAAGGAGUGUGGAGGUGUUUCUCUAAGUCUGGCAGUGAGUUGAGCUCCUUAGGAGGUGGCCAAGAAUAGCAGAUGUUUAGCUCUAAAACUUUGUAUUCAAUGAAGUGAAUAUAAUGAUAUUGCGUAACUUGAAGGCACUUAAAUGUGGUUCUUUAAAAACUGAUAAAAGUGAUGGAAUGUUUACUCUUGUGAUUCAGUCAUUCUAGCACUAAAAUAAAAAGUAGAACAAUUCUCUCUGGCCCUCCUGUUGCCAUCUGACUCCCCAGAAGGAGUUAAUAGUUUGUUUUGCAGAAAUGUCUAGAGAGCCGAGCACUUCUGUGAGUUGGAUGUGGGUUCAGAGAAUCAUAGCAUGUGGCUAAGAGAAGGAGCCCAAGCAUUAAUGAUGAAAUUAAUAAAUUAUGCAGAGUAAGGAAAUACUCUUAUUUAAAGUUAAUGCAUGACAUUAACAAAAGGAUUGAAUGAAAAUGUAGAUAUUUUUCUGCCUCAGGAUUAUAAGAAAAUGAGCCUUGUAACGUCUCAAGGCAGAUGACCCCCAGGGACAAACUUACUUUUUUUUCUUUUGUAUUUUAAAAUAUUGUUAUAUCAUAGUUGUACAUCCAAGGACAACCUUAUUUAUUGUCUCAUUCCUGUGAAUGUGUAGUGUAUAGUAUGUCCUUAGUAAAAAUUGAAGAGAUUCAGAAAAAUUAUCAUCUCUAUAUAGCUAGCCCAUCUUUUUUUCUGGUGGUAUGUGCAACAAAAGCUAUAAUAUGAACUCUGUGUGUGUGUGUGUGAGAGAGAGCGAGAGCGCACACUAGCUAAUUAAUGAAGAACUUGCCAUUCAAUAUUUAUUGUUUUAACUGCUCAUUUAUUCAUAUUCUUGCAUUUUUAAGUAGAACUUUUUAUAUUUUAAUAGUAGAAAAGGGUAUAAUGUAAUAACAGUCUCCUAGCUCACUCCUCCCUGAGUCCCAAUCCUCAGAGAACUAACAAUUUAUUCUGUAUUUAUCUUUAUGUUUCUAUCCUGCUGUCUCUUGAUUUAUCAAUUUAAACUACUCUUGUUAUGGAAGAAAGACAUUUAGUAUUAUAGUCUCACCCCAAUUUUUCCUAUCCUUAUCCCCAAUAUAAUUAUGUCACAAUUUAAAUUCAAAUCGGUAUUGUUGAUGUUGUUAAGAGAAUGUAGAUAAUGGUUUGUUUUCCUGAGUCUAGUUGUGAUUGUUCGUUUUGUAGAUCUGUUUAUUUUUGUUGAUGUUACUUGUUAACUCUUUUUCCCCCCAAUUUGCAGAGCCGUCUUAAUCUAUCGCUGAUUUUCCCUUAGGCACAUGAGUUGACCACGCUAAGGGGGGGUUUCCAAAAUUCCCAUGCCAUUGUCUUCUCUCUUCCAGUGCUGCUUUUGAGAAGUCUGUUGACCAUCCUGAUGGCAGUUACUGUUCAUGGACCAGUUUUUUCUGGAGACUUUUGGGAUCUUUUUGUAUUUUUAAAUUUUACAAAGAGCAUCUUGGAGCUUUGUUUUUCUUCUCUUGCUGGGAGCAGUCCUAUCAGUAUGGAAUAUCUUACCCUUCAUUUCUCCAAAAUAUUUUUAUAUUAUUUCUUUGAUAAUUUGUCUUCCUAUUAUUUUCCUUUCUUUUUGGAACUCCUAUUAUGUAUUAUUUCUCUCUCGUUUUUCAAUUCUUUUUCUUUCCUUUCUAUCUUUCUGGGAGAUUGCUCUGACUUUACUACAAUGCUUUGAUUUGAUUUUUUAAAUUUUGGCAAACUUAUUUUUAAGAAUUCUUUUUUUUUUCUUUUCUUACUGUUACUGUCUCCCUCAAAUAAGAAUGCCUUAUCUUCCUUUCCAGGAAUAUUGAAGAUAAAUAAGUAACUCUAAGGUGUAAAUCAAUGAACUUGACUAGACACUGUCACAAAACUCAUAACAAUAGUAAUCUUAAGCAGUUUUGGUGGGAGUGACAGAAACCCAAUUCAUGCUUAUUGCACUUGCUGCUACCACUAGCAAGAUUAUCCCGAAGGCAAUAAUUCAAGUGAUUAUCUUGUUCAAACAACAACGUAUCUCCCGGAAAACUUCACAUACUCACCAUACCUCCCCUGUCCAGAAAAGCUGCCUUAUAUGCGUGGCAGUUCUCAUUCCUUUCCGUAAUCGCCAUGAACAUCUUCCAAUUUUUUUCUUACAUCUGAUUCCAAUGCUCCAGAAGCAGCGGCUGGAAUUUGCGUUUUAUGUCAUUGAACAGACUGGCACACAACCUUUUAACCGUGCGAUGCUUUUCAAUGUGGGCUUCAAAGAGGCCAUGAAAGACAGUGUCUGGGACUGUGUAAUCUUCCACGAUGUGGAUCAUCUACCUGAAAAUGACCGGAACUAUUACGGAUGUGGAGAAAUGCCACGUCAUUUUGCUGCAAAGCUGGAUAAAUACAUGUAUAUUCUUCCAUAUAAAGAAUUUUUUGGUGGUGUAAGUGGGCUGACAGUGGAACAAUUUAGAAAGAUCAAUGGUUUUCCUAAUGCCUUCUGGGGAUGGGGAGGAGAAGAUGAUGACCUUUGGAACAGAGUUCACUAUGCUGGAUAUAAUGUAACCAGACCAGAGGGAGACUUAGGAAAAUACAAGUCAAUUCCUCAUCACCAUAGAGGUGAAGUCCAGUUUUUAGGACGGUAUAAAUUACUAAGGUAUUCCAAGGAGCGUCAGUACAUCGAUGGACUGAACAAUUUAAUAUAUAGGCCAAAAAUACUGGUUGAUAGGUUGUAUACAAACAUAUCUGUAAACCUCAUGCCAGAGUUAGCUCCAAUCGAAGACUAUUAAAAGAAGUGGCUGUCGUGGCAAGGUAGACCACAAUGCUGGAUCAUAAACUUGGAGCGCGCUCUUAGUGGAGGUCAGUGAUUGGCUGUGUCACAGUGCCCUUUUCUCUGAGAAGAGCCAGCAGUCCACAGUGUUUACAGAGUGGGACUAUAUACAGUCACCCUUCUCUCACCCGUCCUCCCUGCUCUGAGACACACCCCUGUGGCGAGCACCGCAGAAACGGGAAGCCACUACUUAAGAUCGGAAGUUAAGAGAGCUCCCUCCGAAGAGAAAAUUUUUAUACUAAAAUCUAUAAUUUAAUUCAAGAGAAUGCUUUUAUUUCCGUUUAAACAUAUUUUGUAUAUAUGUGAUAUAAAUUAAUGUGUGCAAAUUGUUUAAAAAUUAGAUGUGUUGCAGUUUUGCAUGUAAUCGGUUAUACCUUUAUUGGACUUUUAUAGACAUUUUUUAUUUGCAUGAAAAAAACUCACUAAAUUUACAUCACUAAACAAAGGUUAACCCUUGUGUGAAAUGAAGGAACUGUCAAUAAUUGACAGCCAACUAAUACAGUAAACUGUUAUACUAGUUUUGAGCUUUAGACCUCAGCCUUUUGUGUGGAAGAAGUCACAGCUUUCUUAGGCUUUAAAGGAAAAGAAGGAAGGACUUAAAUAGCUUUUCUUCCUACCGGGAUUACCUAUGUUUUUCCUUGCUUGCAAUCUCAUCUGAUUUUGCUAGAAAUCACAACCAUAUUGUUUAUGCAUAUUGCAUGAGUAUUACCAAGAAAAAUCUUAAAAGUUGUGAUGUGACAUGAUAUAAAGGAUCUCUUUAUGUUAAAUGUCUUUCCAUGUACCUCUGGUGUGUCAGGGAUUUUGUGCCUCAAAAAAUGUUUCCAAGGUUGUGUGUUUAUACUGUGUAUUUUUUUUAAAUUCACGGUGAACAGCACUUUUAUUAUUUCCAGUUCAGAAGAGCCAAAAAAAAGUAUCUUCAUUUAAAAAGAAAUCAAGUCAGUUUUUUUAAAAGAAUGAUCUAUGGAAGAAAACCCAAUAGUACUUAUAAUAUACAAAUGAAUUAUACUAUUAGAUAAGAAUUAAAUAUUCUAUUUUUAUAAAGAUAAAUACUUAGUAGAUAAAAACAAAUUUUAAGUUUAGUUUUCAGACAUAGAAUUUCACUUUUGGAGGGGACCCUUGAAUGUUAGUUUCAUUCAAACUAUAUUUUGUUUUUUUCACUUUUAAGAGAUUAUAUCUCUGGUGUUAAUUACUAAAAUUUUCUUUCUAAAAGUAUAAUUUAAUAGAAUUAUCUUAAAAUACAUGAUCAGUAUUCAGUGCGCUGAUAUUAUAAUGUCUUCUAUAUGUAGUAUCUAAAAGCAUAAUUUAAUAGCAUUGUCUUAAAAUACGUGAUGAGUUAUUUGGUGCACUGAUGCCAUAAUGUCUUCUAUAUGUAAUAUCUUACAUGUUUGCAUGAGUGUCAGGGCUUUGUCCAGUUAUCUUCAUAUGACUGUUCUCUGAAAAAAGGUCUUACUACCUGAUAUCAAGUACAUAUCUUAAUUUUGGAUGAAUUUUUCCACAGUAAAGCCGAACAGUAUUCUUUUUUGAAAAUUAGCAAUUAUAAAGAUUGUUUAAAAUAUCUUGAUAUUUUCACAAAUUUUAAACAAAAAAUUAAAUAUCUAUAAAGUGAAUGUUCAACAACAAUGAUGAGCAAUAGAAAUCUAUAUAUGAGAAACGUUUGGAUAAUAUUUGCCUCAAGGAUUGUUUACCUAAAACAGAACUAUGGUUAUUUAUCUCAGAUUGUAAGUUUUAUUUUGAAGUGUCAUUUUUAUGGCAAUAUUGAUAACACAAAUGACCACAAACUAAAUCAUAAAAUAAUUGAAUCCUUACACUUUGAGAAAAUGGAUAGCUUCUGUGUUAUGAUACCAAACAAAAUAUUUUCAUAUUUAUUUCUUAGAACUAUUUCCAAAAUAUUUAUAUUUCAGUUUUUUUAUGGUACUCGAAAAAUCAAACCUUCUGAAAAUUAUGAUAUUUGUACUUCAUUUGUGUAUUAGUUCAUUUUCUGUUUCUAUUACAUAGUUUUUAAAGUCAAUGAAAGAGAUUGAGAAUGUUAACAUUUGUUGAUCAAUGUGGAGCUGUCCACAUUCGGUAUCUUUUCAUUUUUAUAUAUAUUUUACAGUUUCAAGAAAACUUAGUACUACUAGUAUCUGCCUUAUUUUCUUAAGUCUGAUGUUAAUUUUUGUUUCAGGAGUGAGAUAUAAACAUUUUGCUUUUUUUCAGUUUUGAAAUAUAGUUUGUCAUCCUGUGAAAACCACCUCGUUUGCUUUUUGUUUGUUUGUUUUGCUUUUUUAGUGUAGACCUAAAAUUAUUUUUGCCUAUAAACAGUGAACUUAAUAUGUUUCUGUGAGAGUGACAGAGCUGUGCCCGUUUAUCUUCAUUGUAUUAAUUAUUACAUAAAGAUUAACAAAUACAUUGCAAAUGCAAAUUAUAGGAUGUUUGGAGGAUUUAUUAAUGAGCAUGUAUUGAUUGCCUAUUCCAUAUCCAGUGCAAUGCUAGGUAUGUCUAUGGAAGGAGUAUUAUUACUUCAUUUCUAAACAAAUGAAGUCAAGCAAAUUGAGAUCUUUCUGAAAUUAUGAAGACAUCUUCUGAUAACUUAUCUGUUGUAUUUCCUAGUCUCAAAGUCAAGAAACCCGUAUAUGUGGACCUAGGGCUAAUAGGAGGUCCCUAUGGCACUAACUGGGAAAAUUACAUGGUGCUUUUCAACUACAGAAAGAAGUAAUGACUAAUGGGCCUGUCUGUAGAGAAGAAAAGGAGAAGAGUACACAUUUGCUGGAACUAUAUAUAAUUCACAGUGGAGAUAGUUAAUUCUUUGCUAAAACUAGGGUUUUAUGAGUAUUUUUUAAAUCUACAUUUAAGUUUUUGUUUUUGUGAAAAGUUAUUCAGUAAGAAAACUUUAUAAUAUUAAGUAGAUACAGUUAUGUAUUAAAAAUUUCCUUAUAUACCCUUUUGCCAGCCAAGAUACUGAUAUUUUAAAACAAAAUGGAAAAAUGUCCAAUACAAUAUUCUCUUUCUGGAGGCUUCCUACAAGUGAAAGCAGAUUUUGUCAUUUUAUUUGGCCUUUGCUUGUCUUUGAUAUAUUUCUUUAUGUGUUUUUCAAAUACAUACUGUUGUAGAUUUAUUGUCUUGUAUUUGCAAGUAUGCCGGUUGAGAGAACUAAAAUGGUUAUAGUAUUGUUUAUCAGAAAGAGGAAGUGUACUUAAGAUUAUUUUAUUUAUUUAGAUGAAAGGCUUCUACAUAAAUGCACUGAAAUAAAUGCUAGUAAUUUCUUGUAUCCCACUUCUUUUUUUGCUUCUCAUGGAAAUGUUUGUACUUUUUUAUCAUUGUCUUUUAUGAAAUAUAAUGUUCUAAAGA